AGAUUGGGCAGGAUUCGCGCCUCCAUUUUUCCAGGAGAGAGCGGGAUACCAAGAGAACCGGACCAGCUGGUACUGGGACACGGGGAGAGUAGCUGGUGCGGUCGGCUGGGGCAUUUAGAGAAAACCACAGAAACGACUGGGGCGAGACUGGAAGAGUCGAGAGUUAGCAAGCUGGCAGGGAAACUGUCUUCCUUUUCUCCAAGAUGUACAGAACCAAAGUGGGCUUGAAGGACCGCCAGCAGCUCUACAAGCUGAUCAUUAGCCAGCUGCUAUAUGACGGCUACAUCAGCAUCGCCAAUGGCCUCAUCAAUGAAAUCAAGCCUCAGUCUGUGUGUGCACCCUCGGAGCAGCUCCUGCAUCUCAUCAAACUCGGAAUGGAAAACGAUGACACCGCAGUUCAGUAUGCAAUUGGUCGUUCAGAUACUGUUGCCCCUGGCACAGGGAUUGACCUGGAAUUUGAUGCAGAUGUUCAGACUAUGUCCCCAGAGGCUUCUGAGUACGAAACAUGCUAUGUCACAUCACAUAAAGGACCAUGCCGUGUAGCUACCUAUAGUAGAGAUGGACAGUUAAUAGCUACUGGGUCUGCUGAUGCUUCGAUAAAGAUACUUGACACAGAGAGGAUGUUGGCCAAAAGUGCCAUGCCAAUAGAGGUCAUGAUGAAUGAGACCGCACAACAAAAUAUGGAAAACCACCCAGUGAUUCGAACUCUUUAUGACCAUGUGGAUGAAGUCACGUGCCUUGCUUUCCACCCAACAGAACAGAUCCUGGCUUCUGGUUCAAGGGAUUAUACUCUUAAAUUAUUUGAUUAUUCCAAACCAUCAGCAAAAAGAGCCUUCAAAUACAUUCAGGAAGCUGAAAUGUUACGUUCCAUCUCUUUUCAUCCUUCUGGAGACUUUAUACUUGUCGGAACUCAGCAUCCUACUCUUCGCCUUUAUGAUAUCAACACCUUUCAAUGUUUUGUCUCUUGCAAUCCUCAAGAUCAACACACCGAUGCUAUAUGUUCCGUUAAUUACAAUUCUAGUGCCAAUAUGUACGUAACUGGAAGCAAGGACGGCUGCAUCAAAUUAUGGGAUGGUGUUUCAAAUCGAUGCAUCACAACUUUUGAGAAAGCACAUGACGGUGCUGAAGUUUGUUCUGCCAUUUUUUCCAAAAAUUCUAAAUACAUUCUCUCAAGUGGAAAAGACUCUGUAGCUAAACUUUGGGAAAUAUCAACGGGACGAACACUGGUCAGAUACACGGGCGCGGGUUUAAGUGGACGCCAGGUGCACCGGACACAGGCUGUGUUUAACCACACCGAGGACUAUGUGUUGCUGCCCGACGAGAGGACGAUCAGUCUUUGCUGCUGGGACUCGAGGACAGCCGAGCGGAGAAACCUGCUGUCGUUGGGGCACAACAAUAUUGUACGCUGCAUAGUGCACUCCCCCACCAACCCCGGGUUCAUGACGUGCAGCGAUGACUUCAGAGCGCGGUUUUGGUACCGGAGAUCGACCACUGACUGAGCCACCCUCUCCGUAGGGUUCUUUCUCGAGGACUCUACCCUCCUCCCCCACGUCCUGUCUCAGCUGCAGUCGUAAGUCCGUGCACCAUCCUUGACGUUUUGCUGCCACCUCUGUCCACAUUCUUCUUGGAUUUGUAUAAAAGAAUCUUUUUUUACCUUGAUGUAGAAUCAUGGUGGAAAAAGUUGGAAACACAGAUCUGUGCAGUUCUACAUUCACUGAUUAUUACAGUGUGAUUUUCAUCGGUUUUGUAAGUACAGGACUUGCCGUUUCUUUUGAUCUCUUGAUUGAAGGAGGAUAGGGCAUUAAAGUGCUUUUGACAUGAGGAAUUUUCAUUUGGUUCUUCUGUCAACUUUCUUGCUUAUUCUGCUGAACCCUCUGUGUAUUUCCCUUCCAGGUAUAUUUGAACAGAUAAGCAGGCAUGCAGCUCUGAGACUCCUGAGUUUUAUGCCAUUAUCAAAAGCAUUUUCAAGAAUCCCUCAAUUCUAUCCUGAAAUGAUGUUAUUCUGAUAAUAAAGCUCAGAUCUGCAACUUUAUUGUUAUAUAUUUUUCACUUCUGUAAAAUUAAUGGCCAGUUUUUCCUGACAAUUUAUAGGAACAGUAUCUUUCAACAUACUCCCUACAUUAUCCUUCAAUAUCUGCAAUACUUGUCUUUAGUAACUGUAUUUCUGGUAAGAUUAUGAUUUCAUGAGAAACAAUUGAAAAUAUAUCCGAUCUAAUUAAAUUAGGUCAGCCUGCUAUUGCUCUCAGGUGUUGCCUGUCUUCACGAAUGAUUAGUAUCGAUUGACCUCUUUCUUAGGUGGUUUUAAGUCUUCAGUUCUCGUCAGCAUGAACUAACUUCUCAUCAUGGAGGCACAUAGUAACUGCAUUCUCAGAAGAUUUAUGCAGUUAACCAAUUGAUACAAGUUUUCUUUUUCUUGAAUUUUUUUUUUUUUAAUUGAGGCACAGUCUUGCUCUGUCACCCAGGUUGGAGUGCAGUGGCGUGAUCUCAGCUCACUGCAAGCUCCGCCUCCUGGUUUCACACCAUUUUCCUGCCUCAGCCUCCCAAGUAGCUGGGACUACAGGCACCCACCACCACGCCCGGCUAAUUUUUUUUUUUUUUUUUUUUUUUUUUGUAUUUUUAGUAGAGCCAGGGUUUCACCAUGUUAGCCAGGAUGGUCUCUAUCUCCUGACCUCGUGAUCCGCCUGCCUCAGCCUCCCAAAGUUUUGGGAUUACAGGCGUGAGCCACCGCGCCCAGCCUUCCUGAAGCUUUUUAGAACAUGACAGUACUUCUCUGGAUUCAGCACUAGCAGAGUCAGAGAACUCUGAACUCCCCUUGUACAAACAUAAACUUUGCUUUAUAUUUAUCCCAAAAAACAAAUACCUUAUGAUCUGCAUAGGAGUACCUAGAAAUAUAAUCUGGGAUCAUUUGAUAAAAAUAGUAAAUAGAUUGAAGUAAAAGUCAUUGCUUUAUAUUAUAGGAAGUUUUGUUUUGUUUUGUUUUGUUUGUUUUGUUUUUGAGACGGAGUUUCGCUCUUGUCCCCCAGGCUUUAGUGCAAUGGCGCGAUCUCGGCUCACCGCAGCCUCCGCCACCUGGGUUCAAACGAUUCUCCUGCCUCAGGCUCCCGAGUAACUAGGAUUACAGGCGUGCGCCACCAUGCCCGGCUAAUUUUGUAUUUUUUUUAGUAGAGACGGGGUUUCUCCAUGUUGGUCAGGCUGGUCUCGAACUCCCAACCUCAGGUAAUCCGCCCGCCUCAGCCUCCCAAAGUGCUAGGAUUACAGGCGUGAGCCACCACGCGCGGCCCCAUCAUACGAAGUUACUGAAGUUAUUGCGUAAACAUUCUGUUUUAGUCAUCCUUGAGGAUCGUUUUAACUCCUUGAUCUGUAAAACUGUCUUAAGCAUCUUAACAUGUUACAUCACAGGGUUUUAGCUCAGAUUUCCAAAGAGCCAUAUUUUUUGAUGCAUAUUUCCAGUUGAAUUCCAGUGUGAAUUUCCAGUUGUACUUUGCAUUCUGAUUCUUUGAUAUUUGAACUUGGCCAUCUGUGGGUGCUACUCUCGUAAGACUAAAAGGCACCUACUAAAUACGAACAAGGAUAACCAGUUCUACCAAAAACAUUACCAACCAAACCUCCCCUGUUCUUUUUUCAGACUUUCCUUUUGCUUUCAACCUCUUAAACUGUAAAGGAGAGAUUUAAUGUUUCCCUAUUAUUCUGCUUUGACUCACAUACUAAAAUGACCACAUGGCACUCCAUUGAAUCUUUUCAGUUGUUCACGAAUUAAAAUAAUGCCCAUGUUUUACAGUUUUUCGAGUAGUCUCAGCAAUGGAUCUGUAGUUUCAGGACCUGUUUUUAAAAGAUCAAGAUACUUUUAUGUGUUUCAGAAGUAGCUGUUUUUUCAUUUUUUGUGGGUUUGUUUUUUUUGUGUUUGUUUGGUUGGUUGGUUUUUGGUUUUUUUGCUUUUUAAAGGUCACAGUGUUGUGAGCCUGGUGUAAAUGCCAGGAAUAUUAUAUGGACUUAGUAUCUGCAUCUCGUUAAUUGUACCACACAACACUCUGCCAUUCAAAUAAUGAAUAUCUGGUCAGGAUACGAACUUAUACCCUCUGUGUGUUUUUUUUUUUUAAGAUACGUGAUUUCUGAAAUAAACUUUAUAUACAAUGA